UGAGCUCAGCAGGUAUUGGAAGGUGCCAUGGCUCUGUGAACAUGCACAGGUGGGGAGGCUGGGGUGGGGGCAGAGCAGGGGACAGUCCUGGAGCCAGCAGACAGGAGGAGGCAUCUCUACAGCACCCCAGGCUUGGAGACAGGGCUGGCUCACCUCAAAGGGGGCCAUGGGAGAGAGGAAGGUGGGCAUCAGGGCUGGCCUGCCCCGGCCCCAGGAAUACGUGGGAGUUGAGCUGCAUGAGGGGUGGCCAGCCUAGGGCAGGGCAGGAGCCACGGGGCGUCCGCUCCUCUCUGUGGGUUUCGGUGUGGGAGGAGGAAGGACAAGCUCCUCCUGGAAGCAAAGGGGCCUGAGGACCCAGGAGCAGAGUGACCUUGUGGGCAGGGCCGUCCCUGAGGCCUGCCACAUGCAGAGGACGUGGCCCCUGUGGCCAGCUUGGUGCCAGGAGCAGGUCCUGGGGGGUGGGGAGUAAGUCUCCCAGGGGCCGAGCUCCAUGAGUACACGUGGUGUGGACACUGGGCCUGCCACAGGGAGGCUGGUGUGGGCAGGAGGCUCCCUGGGAAGUGGAGAAGCGCUUUCUGUGAGCUUGUUCCAGGGCUCUGGUCAGCCCAGCCUGGGGUCUCAUGGCCACGCAGGUCAGCAGGAAGGGGAAGAUGCCCCAGCAAGGAGGCAGGAAGGCGGCCUCUGCCCGGCGCAUCAGUCUCGGAGGUGGGGGACCCAGGGUUUGUUCUCAGCAGGCCUCCUCUCCUCCUCUGCCUCACAGUCACCUCUGGGAUGGGAGAGGCGGUGUCUGCAGGGCCCUUCCCACAAAGUCUGUCCAUCUGCCCCUGCUGCUGCUGCAAGGGGCUACGGGUCCUCUGGCGACUCUGGACCCCCCGGAAAAGGGAGGCUUGAGCUGCCCACUGCACCCUUGACCCCUUCUGAGCCUCUCAGCAAAGUCCCAAUCCACCCUCCUCAGGAGGUCCCAGGGAUUUGCCCACAUGGGCACCCCAUGCCCUCAGCCAACCAACCCCACCAUGGCCCACACGCCUGCCCCUCCCUCUGUCUCCUUGGGGCCCCGCACACGUUGGCACAGAACAUCUCCCUGCUGGGUGACCUCUUCCCGCGAGCGGCCCAGGACAAGUGCAGCCUUCUGGGCAGACACAGGGAGCGGGCGUUCCCGAUUCACAGAGGACUCACCUCGGCGUACUACAGCAGCCUGGCAGAGCCCAGCCUGCGACAAGGGCCUCAUAUGCAUCUGUUGAGUACACCAGUGAAUCCCAAUCCCCUAGUUCGUUUUCUACCCCAGAGGCCCAACAACUGGGUGGGGUGGGGGAGGCAUUUCGCUGGACGCCGUGGAGACGCAGUAUCGUCCGGGAACCUGAGUCUCCGUAAACCCCGGGGUUGGACAGACCAGUGCCAGCAAGCUCCUUCACAGAGAGGAACUCAGACACGAAUCCCUGGAGACUCCUAGUUCUCAUACAGAGCUUGUUUUUUCACUUCCAUUUUCAAAGUCCGGAUUUUCACAGGUCUGCUUCUCCCGGGGGCCACGCCUGCAUUUCUGCGAACGAUCCCCAGCUGUCGCUAAUGAAACGCUCCUCCACUGAGAGGGAGCCCAGCCCCACUCAAGCCGGUCAGAGCUCAUCCGUAGGAGGCUGUGUGGGGGUCACGCCACCACAGGACGCAGAUCUGCCCGAAGCCUGUUUUAUUGCACUUAACUAAUUCCCAAGAUAAACCACUGGGAAUUUCCAUAUUUCCACUUCUGCUACCACCGGGAUGGAAAAGGCCUCUUCCCUCAGAUUCCCCCAAUCCCAAGAAUGCAAUUCCUUCACUAAUGCUGAGUGGAGACAUAGUCUCUACAAUCCAGAAGGCUGAGUGAGGUGGAAACGUCGGUGCAGCCUGCAGCUCACCUGGUUGUCACUCGUAGAUCGGCCUCGGAAAGCUCCAGGAAGUUGGUUUGGGAUGAGCCGGGCGUCCUGCACAGAUGGUGGGAGGGAGAGGAGGCCGGAGCUUCAGCCAGUGCAGCGCCAUGGCCCCUGUUCUGUGGUUCACUGGGGUGUGAGGCCUUCCUUGGGCUCAGAGAGGGGGCCUCCGAGUCCUCAUCCACAGAAGCCCUCUGUGCCACCAGCAGGGAACAGCCAGCAAAGAGCCUUCACCCUGAAGAUCCAGACGGAAUUCUUGGUUUCUACAGCUGCUCCCUGCCUCUCCCCACAGCCACGGGAAGGGGAGUUAACCGAGGCAGCCCCCACCCGAGACAGACCUGCACAGGGCCAAGAACUUGCCCUGUGGUAGGGCUGGGGGAGGAGCGGCUGGUGGACUUUCUGUGUCAAAGGCAGGUGUCACUUUCAGCUCAUUAAUUUCACUUCUCCAGGUUCUCAAUCCACCAAAAUGAGCUCUUUACAAAGGCCAGGACCUGCCCUUCUAGAGGACAGGCUCAUACUUCCCAAAGCUUCAGGACUUCGGGUCCUGUGGCUGCCCAUCCGUCAGCAGAACUGGGUGAGGCCAGGUGUGACAUCAGACAAGUCCCCCGCCUCUGGCAAUUCCUCAGCGGGGGGCAUGACCUACUGUGCAUUCCAGGGCUGCGGCACAUGUACUUACCCCUUAGCCUUGGACCACAAGCCUCCCCCAGCCCAAAAUGGAAUGGGGACAGCCUCUGCCACAGGGAGGGGCAGGUGGUGCCGUGUGAGGGGCGGUGGCACCCAGGGCUUUUCUCACAAGGAAAAGGAACCUCAAAGUGUUUCUCUCUGCACACUUUGCCUCCCUCAAAUGCGGGCUCCUUCCUCUCCCACCCGCAUCAGCAGCUGAGGCCCCAGAAGGGCCCACCUGUGUCCCGCCCACCAUGCGUGAGAUCGCUGAUUGCCUCCUGGGAUAGUGGCAGCGUGCUCGAGCCUCUCCGGACCGCAUCCCAGCUGUUAGAACCAGGAAGCCCCCGUCAGGCACCAAGACCCCCAGACGCUGGCCCGGGCUCCCCAUUUUCACUUGAUCCUCUCCGCCGUGUUUCUGUCUUCCUGGGGCUGCAGGCGUUUUGGUCAUGGCUGCAUCACACCAGAGUCUGCGUCCGUGGCCACGCAGCCUCCUCCUUUUCUCCGUGUCUUAAACUUCUUUCUGUUCCCUCUUAUCGGGACCUCCUGAUGCCAUCAGACGCCGCCCCACCAUGGUUCAGAACAAUCUUUCCAUCUCAAGAUCCUCAGUUCAAUCACAUCUGCAGAGACCCUUUUUUUCUGUGUAAAGUAGCAUUCACAGGUCCCAGGGAUUAGGAUCUGAUAUCUCUGGGGCCAGUACAGAUGGGUUUGAGAUUUGAUCAUGGAGAAAAGAAAUGACGGCAUUUAGCUCUAUAUCCUAGUCAACACGGAGCCGCGAGCAUGAUUGAGAAGAACGUCAAAGAUCAAGCAGUUUUGUAAAAGAGUAAAGCCCCUCCACUCUCCUAAACCCAGCCAAUUUCUCAAAAUUUGUGAGAGCGGCGUCCUCCCAGCAGCAAACACAAGGGACACGUGUGUGCACCCAGACCAGCACCUACCACUCUAGACAGUCCCCAGAGCGAGGCUUAGGACUGACGGCCGGAGAUGCAACCGUGGCCAGGGGCCCAGAGCUCAUUGAAACCUGCUCAGUCCAAGGCCUUAGGCUGAGCCUGACAUCGUGUCGUAUUGUGGAAACACUCGUUCCCUCAUUCAGCCGAAUGCUUUUUAAAGCGACUUUUUGGCUGGGCACGGUGGCUCGCGCCUGUCAACCCAGCACUUCGGGAGGCCGAGGUGGGAGGAUCAUUUGAGGUCAGGAGUGUGAGACCAGCCUGACCAAUAUGGUAAAACCCUGUCUCUACUAAAAUACAAAAAAAAAAAAAAA